GCAUUUGACCAAGCCGUGACCAAGGACACCUGCAUGGCGGUUGGCUUCUUCCAGCGAGGAGUGGCCAACUUCCAGCUGGCAAGGUGAGUACAGGGGUGCCUUGUUCCUUCUCUGACGGCCCUUUGUCUCCCUGCAGAGUCCACUCCUGCACCUCCUCCUCCUCCCUCUCCAUCCACUCCCUCCUCUUGCCCACCCCCUCCUCCAUGGUUCCUGGCUCCAGGGAAACCUGAGACUGUGGCCCUCGCCUCUGCUGAGCGCCACCCUUGGACACAGGUCGUGGGGUCCUCACUGCUUACCUGGGCUCUCUGCACCAUGUCCCUUCCUAAAGGAGGAAUGAGGGAAAGGAGACCAUCGGGACUGCAGACCAGGCCAUGCCUCGGCCUCUCUGCUAGACACUCACAGGCCCCAUCCCAGGAGGGCAGGCUCUGUGGGGAAGUGGAUCACAGUCCCGAGAGCCUCGCAAUCCUGAAAUAUCAAAACCCCUCAAAUCUAAAAUCCCAAAAAAUAUAAUUCUAGAAAAAAUAAAAUUCUGUAAAAGAUAUUUAUUUACUUUUUAAAAAUUGUUUUGAGAAGGAGCCUUGCUCUGUCAUCCAGGCUGGAGUGCAAUUGUGCGAUCUCGGCUCACUGCAACCUCCGCCUCCUGGGUUCAAGCGAUUCUCCUGCCUUAGCCUCCCGGGUAGCUGGGAUUACAGGCAUGUGCCACCACGCCUGGCUAAUUUUUGUAUUUUUAGUAGAGACUGGGCAUCACCAUGUUGGCCAGGCUGGUCUCGAACUCCUGACCUCAGGUGAUCCACCCGCCUCGGCCUCCCAAAGUGCUGGGAUUACAGGAAUGAGCCACCUCGCCCAGCCUAUUUACAUAUUUUAAAGGGAUUUAUUUGAGAAACAUAAAAACACGACGGAACCCUUCAUUGGCCGAUAAAAUAGACAAAAAUAACAUACAUAUUUUUUCAAGCACAAAUUCAUGCACGCUAGCGACAGGCUCACGGGUGUGAGAACUACGAGCAGAUGAACAGUGCUCAUGAGGAGCUAGGUCAGAAGGGGUAAGACGUAGGUGCGUAGACUCUGGCUGGUGACUGUGUGCACCUGGCUUUAUAACUGGUCAUCAAAACACCAAGAUGAACAACCCACCUUCUAACAAGAUCCAUCAAAGGCUUCAGGGACCACCACAUACGCAGUCGCCCAGAGAGCCCGGAUCUGGAGAUAUUUUACCUUUCAGAAAGGCAGAUGAACGAAAAAGCCAUCUCUUCCUUUACUGAAGAGUCCCAGCAUUCGGGAUUAUGGCUGUGGGACUGUCCCUUUCUGGAUUACGAUCCAGACCCCUCUGGGGCAGCCUCUCCUUCACAUCGGCGCGGGAAGCCCGCCUGGAGGAGAGGCCUCUCCGGCAGGCGCUGGGGAGCUCCCAGCAAGGCUUGGAAGGAGGCUCAGAGUUUGGAGGGGGAGCCCCCAUGGGGUGGGGGGCCUGAGAAGCAGGAGGGAAAUAACCAGGGCUCUCUGCACGGUUCAGAAGAGAGGCUUGGGGGCGGGCAGGGGCCCAGGAAGCUGAGUCUGAGCUGGGAAAAUGGUGGAGCCCCAGCACACAGUGACCCCCACACCCACUCAGCACACAUGUGCAUGGACCCCUGGCCCACCAGACCUGAGUGUGCAGACCUAGGCACCGCACUGCCCUCCCUCAGGUCUCCUUGGAACCAGGUGUUGGGGGCGGCUCGAGCGGGGCUGGUGUGAAAGCUGCCUAACCACAGCCCCAUCUCCGCCCUGUGCUGCUGAGGGGACCCCGGCUGCCCACAGGUUCCAGGAGGCUCUGUCUGACUUCUGGCUGGCCCUGGAGCAGCUGAGGGGCCACGCUGCCAUCGACUACACGCAGCUGGGCCUGCGGUUCAAGCUGCAAGCCUGGGAGCCCUUUCCUGGCUGCCUGGAACGUGUUGGCACCGAAGGAGGGGUGCUGAGAGGCCCCCCCACCAGACCCCGGAAAUGCAUCGCCCUGAAGCCUUCUGGGAAUAGCAUUGUCUUUUAGGACAAAAAGAUGGAAGGGAAAGCCCACUGGUGUGGGUCUGGAGUCAGGGUUAAAGCCAGGUGCUACACAAUGUGGCGUCGGCACAGUGCCAGCUGGGGCUCUGGACAGAGGCGGCCAGCAGCCUAAGGGAGGCCAUGUCCAAGUGGCCGGAGGGGUCCCUGAAUGGCCUGGACUCAGCCCUGGACCAAGUGCAGAGACGGGGCUCACUGCCGCCACGGCAGGUCCCCAGGGGCGAGGUCUUCCGGCCCCACCGGUGGCACCUGAAGCACUUGGAGCCCGUGGAUUUCCUGGGCAAGGCCAAGGUGGUGGCCUCUGCCAUCCCCGACGACCAGGGCUGGGGCGUCCGCCCUCAGCAGCCACAGGGACCAGGAGCGAACCAUGAUGCCAGGUCCCUAAUCAUGGACUCCCCAAGAGCUGGCACCCACCAGGGCCCCCUCGAUGCAGAGACAGAGGUCGGUGCUGACCGCUGCACGUCGACUGCCUACCAGGAGCAGAGGCCCCAGGUGGAGCAAGUUGGCAAACAGGCUCCUCUCUCCCCAGGGCUGCCGGCAAUGGGGGGGCCUGGCCCCGGCCCCUGUGAGGACCCCGCGGGUGCUGGGGGAGCAGGUGCAGGGGGCUCCGAGCCCCUGGUGACUGUCACCGUGCAGUGCGCCUUCACAGUGGCCCUGAGGGCACGAAGAGGAGCCGACCUGUCCAGCCUGCGGGCACUGCUGGGCCAAGCCCUCCCUCACCAGGCCCAGCUUGGGCAACUCAGUUACCUAGCCCCAGGUGAGGACGGGCACUGGGUCCCCAUCCCCGAGGAGGAGUCGCUGCAGAGGGCCUGGCAGGACGCAGCUGCCUGCCCCAGGGGGCUGCAGCUGCAGUGCAGGGGAGCCGGGGGUCGGCCGGUCCUCUACCAGGUGGUGGCCCAGCACAGCUACUCCGCCCAGGGGCCAGAGGACCUGGGCUUCCGACAGGGGGACACGGUGGACGUCCUGUGUGAAGAGCCCGAUGUCCCCCUUGCAGUGGACCAGGCAUGGCUGGAGGGCCACUGUGACGGCCGCAUCGGCAUCUUCCCCAAGUGCUUCGUGGUCCCCGCCGGCCCUCGGAUGUCAGGAGCCCCCGGCCGCCUGCCCCGAUCCCAGCAGGGAGAUCAGCCCUAAUGAUGCUGUGUCCAUGAUGCUUUUAAUAAAAACAACCCCCACUGCA